GGAGCGGCUGCACGGACAAGAGCGGAGGCCUGGAGAAAUCAACUUUUCAGUAAUUGGUCAGUAUGUGGAUUAUCUUGUGAAAGAACAGGGAGUGAAGAACAUUUUUGUGAAUGGCACAACAGGAGAAGGCCUGUCCCUGAGCGUCUCAGAGCGUCGCCAGGUUGCAGAGGAGUGGGUGACAAAAGGGAAGGACAAGUGAGUGGCUGCAUGAGGAUAAAAAUGCCCUUUGGCAACAGCUGUAUUCAGUGAGCCUCUUCCCCAGAGGAUACGCCCUCCCUGCUUCCUGGUCAGAGCCGGGGCUUGAGGUCAGCUGGUGGGAAGAUGAGCAGGGCCCCCGGGAUCCUGGCUUCUUGGAGAAGAGCCCCCUCCCUUUCUGUGCAGAAGGGCAGCCAAACUGCUAGACACACCUGCCACCCAGAGGUUCCGCUGGGAAACUGCUUCUUACCUGUCUACAAGGCCAGUCCCCUCACAGUUACCCGUCUUUGGGCUGAAAGGCUGGAUCAGGUGAUAAUUCACGUAGGAGCACUGAGCUUGAAGGAGUCACAGGAACUGGCCCAACAUGCAGCAGAAAUAGGAGCUGAUGGCAUCGCUGUCAUUGCACCGUUCUUCCUCAAGCCAUGGACCAAAGAUAUCCUGAUUAAUUUCCUAAAGGAAGUGGCUGCUGCCGCCCCUGCCCUGCCAUUUUAUUACUAUCACAUUCCUGCCUUGACAGGGGUAAAGAUUCGUGCUGAGGAGUUGUUGGAUGGGAUUCUGGAUAAGAUCCCCACCUUCCAAGGGCUGAAAUUCAGUGAUACAGAUCUCUUAGACUUCGGGCAAUGUGUUGAUCAGAAUCGCCAGCAACAGUUUGCUUUCCUUUUUGGGGUGGAUGAGCAACUGUUGAGUGCUCUGGUGAUGGGAGCAACUGGAGCAGUGGGCAGUACCUAUAACUACCUGGGAAAAAAGACAAACCAGAUGUUGGAGGCUUUUGAACAAAAGGACUUCUCUUUAGCCCUGAACUAUCAGUUUUGUAUCCAGAGAUUUAUCAACUUUGUUGUCAAACUAGGUUUUGGAGUGUCACAGACCAAAGCCAUCAUGACUCUGGUCUCUGGGAUUCCAAUGGGCCCACCCCGGCUUCCACUGCAGAAAGCCUCCAGGGAGUUUACUGAUAGUGCUGAAGCUAAACUGAAGAGCCUGGAUUUCCUUUCUUUCACUGAUUUAAAGGAUGGAAACUUGGAAGCUGGUAGCUAGUGCCUCUCUAUCAAAUCAGGGUUUGCACCUUGAGACAUAAUCUACCUUAAAUAGUGCAUUUUUUUCUCAGGGAAUUUUAGAUGAACUUGAAUAAACUCUCCUAGCAAAUGAAAUCUCACAAUAAGCAUUGAGGUACCUUUUGUGAGCCUUAAAAAGUCUUAUUUUGUGAAGGGGCAAAAACUCUAGGAGUCACAACUCUCAGUCAUUCAUUUCACAGAUUUUUUUGUGGAGAAAUUUCUGUUUAUAUGGAUGAAAUGGAAUCAAGAGGAAAAUUGUAAUUGAUUAAUUCCAUCUGUCUUUAGGAGCUCUCAUUAUCUCGGUCUCUGGUUCCUAAUCCUAUUUUAAAGUUGUCUAAUUUUAAACCACUAUAAUAUGUCUUCAUUUUAAUAAAUAUUCAUUUGGAAUCUAGGAAAACUCUGAGCUACUGCAUUUAGGCAGGCACUUUAAUACCAAACUGUAACAUGUCUCAACUGUAUACAACUCAAAAUACACCAGCUCAUUUGGCUGCUCAGUCUAACUCUAGAAUGGAUGCUUUUGAAUUCAUUUCGAUGUCACCACUUUUCGCUCUUUAAAAACACUGGGUCAGGUGAGGACUUGUUUCAGUUCCUAUAACUAAGUAAAGGGCGGCUUUCUCAUAACAAAGGAAAAAGUCUUCCCCAAAGAUGAAUUUAAGUCUCCACUUUUUUCUAUACAGAAAACUCAAAACUCAAAGUUUCAAAGAACCAAAGGACUCUUCCUCUGGGCACCACAAACUUCCCCUUCCUCCACUGAGAAGACUGUCUCUCCCGCAGGACCCUGAAUUAUUGAAAUCGAAGGCUGACUUCCUUUCUGCAGUGAGCCCAGGGGCUAAUGUUAUUAUCCUGUCACACUUGCAACUAGUGACUUUUGUUUAGUGAUAGAAGAUUUGGGGAGGACCCAAAGGACUCAGAACUUUCUCUCCAUACCUCCUUUUACUCUUUUCUUUCUGUGUAAUGUAUCAACAACUGUUUAAUCUCCCUUCUAACAAACCUUGAUAUAAGCUUUCUGAUAUCAAAGUAUAUUGACAGUUAACCCUUACUGAUUUUAAACUUGACUAUCCAGUCUGUUAAUUACCUAAGAUUUUGUUUUCAUUUCAUCUCUAAUUGUUUUGAUCAUUGGCAGAGAAAGAGUAUUUGAAAUUCAUAUCAGUUUUGCUCCUUAUUUUAAUCUCUUUGAAUUAAAAAUAAAACUUUUUCAAAAUGGAAAUUUGAAAUUAUAAGUAGACUUCAAUUAUCUUUGCUAAUCCUCUCUUUAAUUAGUCAGCUAGUUAAAAGUUGUUAUAUUCAUAUAUCCUCAACCCUCUUUUUGCCUUUGUAGCUUUUAAUUUCCUGAAAGAAGAAAAUGAGUUGUUCGUUUUUGGUUCUGAGGAUGUGAUAUCCGUACUUACUGAUACUAAAGCCAAAUUUAAAUUCUAAAAUUAAUUCUUGGGUAUCCAAUAAACAAAGAACUAUUUUUCUA